AGCAGAGCAAUCACCACCAAGCCUGGAAUAACUGCAAGGGCUCUGCUGACAUCUUCCUGAGGUGCCAAGGAAAUGAGGAUGGAGGAAGGAAUGAAUGUUCUCCAUGACUUUGGGAUCCAGUCAACACAUUACCUCCAGGUGAAUUACCAAGACUCCCAGGACUGGUUCAUCUUGGUGUCCGUGAUCGCAGACCUCAGGAAUGCCUUCUACGUCCUCUUCCCCAUCUGGUUCCAUCUUCAGGAAGCUGUGGGCAUUAAACUCCUUUGGGUAGCUGUGAUUGGAGACUGGCUCAACCUCGUCUUUAAGUGGAUUCUCUUUGGACAGCGUCCAUACUGGUGGGUUUUGGAUACUGACUACUACAGCAACACUUCCGUGCCCCUGAUAAAGCAGUUCCCUGUAACCUGUGAGACUGGACCAGGGAGCCCCUCUGGCCAUGCCAUGGGCACAGCAGGUGUAUACUACGUGAUGGUCACAUCUACUCUUUCCAUCUUUCAGGGAAAGAUAAAGCCGACCUACAGAUUUCGGUGCUUGAAUGUCAUUUUGUGGUUGGGAUUCUGGGCUGUGCAGCUGAAUGUCUGUCUGUCACGAAUCUACCUUGCUGCUCAUUUUCCUCAUCAAGUUGUUGCUGGAGUCCUGUCAGGCAUUGCUGUUGCAGAAACUUUCAGCCACAUCCACAGCAUCUAUAAUGCCAGCCUCAAGAAAUAUUUUCUCAUUACCUUCUUCCUGUUCAGCUUCGCCAUCGGAUUUUAUCUGCUGCUCAAGGGACUGGGUGUAGACCUCCUGUGGACUCUGGAGAAAGCCCAGAGGUGGUGCGAGCAGCCAGAAUGGGUCCACAUUGACACCACACCCUUUGCCAGCCUCCUCAAGAACCUGGGCACGCUCUUUGGCCUGGGGCUGGCUCUCAACUCCAGCAUGUACAGGGAGAGCUGCAAGGGGAAACUCAGCAAGUGGCUCCCAUUCCGCCUCAGCUCUAUUGUAGCCUCCCUCGUCCUCCUGCACGUCUUUGACUCCUUGAAACCCCCAUCCCAAGUCGAGCUGGUCUUCUACGUCUUGUCCUUCUGCAAGAGUGCGGUAGUGCCCCUGGCAUCCGUCAGUGUCAUCCCCUACUGCCUCGCCCAGGUCCUGGGCCAGCCGCACAAGAAGUCGUUGUAAGAGAUGUGGAGUCUUCGGUGUUUAAAGUCAACAACCAUGCCAGGGAUUGAGGAGGACUACUAUUUGAAGCAAUGGGCACUGGUAUUUGGAGCAAGUGACAUGCCAUCCAUUCUGCCGUCGUGGAAUUAAAUCACGGAUGGCAGAUUGGAGGGUCGCCUGGCUUAUUCCCAUGUGUGACUCCAGCCUGCCCUCAGCACAGACUCUUUCAGAUGGAGGUGCCAUAUCACGUACACCAUAUGCAAGUUUCCCGCCAGGAGGUCCUCCUCUCUCUACUUGAAUACUCUCACAAGUAGGGAGCUCACUCCCACUGGAACAGCCCAUUUUAUCUUUGAAUGGUCUUCUGCCAGCCCAUUUUGAGGCCAGAGGUGCUGUCAGCUCAGGUGGUCCUCUUUUACAAUCCUAAUCAUAUUGGGUAAUGUUUUUGAAAAGCUAAUGAAGCUAUUGAGAAAGACCUGUUGCUAGAAGUUGGGUUGUUCUGGAUUUUCCCCUGAAGACUUACUUAUUCUUCCGUCACAUAUACAAAAGCAAGACUUCCAGGUAGGGCCAGCUCACAAGCCCAGGCUGGAGAUCCUAACUGAGAAUUUUCUACCUGUGUUCAUUCUUACCGAGAAAAGGAGAAAGGAGCUCUGAAUCUGAUAGGAAAAGAAGGCUGCCUAAGGAGGAGUUUUUAGUAUGUGGCGUAUCAUGCAAGUGCUAUGCCAAGCCAUGUCUAAAUGGCUUUAAUUAUAUAGUAAUGCACUCUCAGUAAUGGGGGACCAGCUUAAGUAUAAUUAAUAGAUGGUUAGUGGGGUAAUUCUGCUUCUAGUAUUUUUUUUACUGUGCAUACAUGUUCAUCGUAUUUCCUUGGAUUUCUGAAUGGCUGCAGUGACCCAGAUAUUGCACUAGGUCAAAACAUUCAGGUAUAGCUGACAUCUCCUCUAUCACAUUACAUCAUCCUCCUUAUAAGCCCAGCUCUGCUUUUUCCAGAUUCUUCCACUGGCUCCACAUCCACCCCACUGGAUCUUCAGAAGGCUAGAGGGCGACUCUGGUGGUGCUUUUGUAUGUUUCAAUUAGGCUCUGAAAUCUUGGGCAAAAUGACAAGGGGAGGGCCAGGAUUCCUCUCUCAGGUCACUCCAGUGUUACUUUUAAUUCCUAGAGGGUAAAUAUGACUCCUUUCUCUAUCCCAAGCCAACCAAGAGCACAUUCUUAAAGGAAAAGUCAACAUCUUCUCUCUUUUUUUUUUUUUUUGAGACAGGGUCUCACUAUGUUGCCCAGGCUGCUCUUGAAUUCCUGGGCUCAAGCAGUCCUCCCACCCUACCACAGCGUCCCGCGUAGCUGGGACUACAGGUGCAAGCCACUAUGUCCAGCUAGCCAACUCCUCCUUGCCUGCUUUUCUUUUUUUUUCUUUUUUUGAGACGGCGCACCUAUCACCCAGGCUGGAGUGGAGUGGCACGAUCUUGGCUCACUGCAACCUCUUCCUCCUGGUUCAAGCGAUUCUCAUGUCUCAGCCUCCUCAGUAGCUAGGACUACCGGCGUGCACCACCAUGCCAGGCUAAUUUUUAUAUUUUUAGAAUUUUAGAAGAGAUGGGAUUUCAUCAUGUUGGCCAGGCUGGUCUCGAACUCCUGACCUCAAGUGAUCCACCUGCCUUGGCCUCCCAAGGUGCUAGGAUUACAGGCAUGAGCCACCGCACCGGGCCCUCCUUGCCUGUUUUUCAAUCUCAUCUGAUAUGCAGAGUAUUUCUGCCCCACCCACCUACCCCCCAAAAAAAGCUGAAGCCUAUUUAUUUGAAAGUCCUUGUUUUUGCUACUAAUUAUAUAGUAUACCAUACAUUAUCAUUCAAAACAACCAUCCUGCUCAUAACAUCUUUGAAAAGAAAAAUAUAUAUGUGCAGUAUUUUAUUAAAGCAACAUUUUAUUUAAGAAUAAAGUCUUGUUAAUUACUAUAUUUUAGAUGCAAUGUGAUCUGAAGUUUCUAAUUCUGGCCCAACUAAAUUUCUAGCUCUGUUUCCCUAAACAAAUAAUUUGGUUUCUCUGUGCCUGCAUUUUCCCUUUGGAGAAGAAAAGUGCUCUCUCUUGAGUUGACCGAGAGUCCCAUUAGGGAUAGGGAGACUUAAAUGCAUCCACAGGGGCACAGGCAGAGUUGAGCACAUAAACGGAGGCCCAAAAUCAGCAUAGAACCAGAAAGAUUCAGAGUUGGCCAAGAAUGAACAUUGGCUACCAGACCACAAGUCAGCAUGAGUUGCUCUAUGGCAUCAAAUUGCAACUUGAGAGUAGAUGGGCAGGGUCACUAUCAAAUUAAGCAAUCAGGGCACACAAGUUGCAGUAACACAACAAGACUAGGCCAGCUCUGGAAUCCAGUAACUCAGUGUCAGCAAGGUUUUGGGUUAUAGUUCAAGAAAGUCUAAACAGAGCCAGUCACAGCACCAAGGAAUGCUCAAGGGAGCUAUUGCAGGUUUCUCUGCUAAGAGAUUUAUUUCAUCCUGGGUGCAGGGUUCGACCUCCAAAGGCCUCAAAUCAUCACCGUAUCAAUGGAUUUCCUGAGGGUAAGCUCCGCUAUUUCACACCUGAACUCCGGAGUCUGUAUAUUCAGGGAAGAUUGCAUUCUCCUACUGGAUUUGGGCUCUCAGAGGGCGUUGUGGGAACCAGGCCCCUCACAGAAUCAAAUGGUCCCAACCAGGGAGAAAGAAAAUAGUCUUUUUUUUUUUUUUAAUAGAGAUGGGGGUCUCACUAUGCUGCCCAGGCUGGUCUUGAACUCCUGGGUUCAAGUGAUCCUCCUGCCUCAGCCUCCCAAAGUGCUGGGAUUACAGUGUGAGCCACUGCGCUUGGCCAGAAAUGGUUUUGAUCUGUCUGAACUGAACCCUACUGCUUAGGCAUAGCCCCAUCCUUGAUAAUCUAUUUGCUCCCAAGGACCAAGUCCAAGAUCCUUACAAGAAAGGUCUGCCAGAAAGUAAAUACUGCCCCCACUCCCUGAAGUUUAUGAGGUUGAUAAGAAAACAUAACAGAUAAAGUUUAUUGAGUGCUAACUUUAUGCCA